ACUCCACUCCCGGCACGCCCGGUGCCGCCUUCCGGCUCCAGUCCCCGGGCUCGGCCUCGGCGAGGUGUAAUUCGCAGCGCGGGCCGGCCCCGGAGGCUCUCGGCGAGCGCGGCGCGGUAACAAGUGGGCGAGGAUGCCGUACGAGAUCAAGAAGGUGUUCGCCAGCCUCCCGCAGGUGGAGAGGGGCGUCUCCAAGAUCAUCGGCGGCGACCCUAAGGGCAACAAUUUUCUGUACACCAAUGGAAAGUGCGUCAUCCUAAGGAACAUCGACAACCCAGCCCUUGCUGACAUCUACACAGAGCACGCCCAUCAGGUGGUGGUGGCCAAGUAUGCGCCCAGCGGAUUCUACAUUGCCUCCGGAGAUGUGUCUGGGAAGCUGAGGAUCUGGGAUACCACGCAGAAGGAGCACCUGUUGAAGUAUGAGUACCAGCCUUUCGCUGGGAAGAUCAAAGACAUUGCUUGGACUGAAGACAGUAAGAGGAUCGCCGUGGUCGGGGAAGGAAGGGAGAAGUUUGGAGCAGUCUUCCUCUGGGAUAGUGGCUCUUCUGUGGGCGAGAUUACAGGACACAACAAAGUCAUCAACAGCGUGGACAUCAAGCAGAGCCGGCCAUACCGGCUGGCCACGGGAAGCGAUGAUAACUGCGCGGCAUUCUUUGAGGGACCCCCAUUCAAGUUCAAGUUCACAAUUGGCGACCACAGCCGCUUUGUCAACUGUGUGCGAUUCUCUCCUGAUGGGAACAGAUUUGCCACAGCCAGUGCUGACGGCCAGACUCGUCGUCAGAGCCCAGUAAAUGCAUGUCUGCUUUUAAACCACACUGGGAGCUUAGUCUGUGAGCCCCGGUUUUCUACAGCCACAGUCCAUGGAGAAACUGCUUACUCCAGAGGGUGUUCACACACACAUGACCCACAUGUUUUUAUUUCUUGGAAGAUAUACAUCUAUGACGGGAAGACUGGGGAGAAGGUGUGCGCGCUGGGCGGAAGCAAGGCCCACGACGGUGGGAUUUACGCAAUUAGUUGGAGUCCCGACAGCACCCAUUUGCUUUCUGCUUCUGGGGACAAAACUUCCAAGAUUUGGGACGUCAGCGUGAACUCCGUGGUCAGCACAUUUCCCAUGGGCUCCACGGUUCUGGACCAGCAGCUGGGCUGCCUAUGGCAGAAGGACCACCUGCUCAGUGUCUCCCUGUCCGGGUACAUCAACUAUCUGGACAGAAACAACCCCAGCAAGCCCCUGCACGUCAUCAAGGGUCACAGUAAAUCGAUCCAGUGUCUGACGGUGCAUAAAAACGGCGGCAAGUCCUACAUUUACUCUGGGAGCCACGACGGACACAUUAAUUACUGGGAUUCAGAGACGGGGGAGAACGACUCCUUCGCUGGGAAAGGCCACACGAACCAGGUGUCCAGGAUGACCGUGGAUGAGUCGGGGCAGCUCAUCAGCUGCAGCAUGGACGACACCGUGCGGUACACCAGCCUCAUGCUGCGGGACUACAGCGGACAAGGAGUUGUGAAACUGGACGUUCAGCCAAAGUGCGUAGCCGUCGGCCCCGGGGGAUACGCCGUGGUCGUGUGCAUUGGACAGAUUGUCCUGCUGAAGGAUCAGAGGAAGUGCUUCAGCAUCGACAACCCCGGCUACGAGCCCGAAGUUGUGGCAGUGCACCCCGGCGGGGACACGGUGGCAAUUGGGGGUGUGGACGGCAACGUCCGCCUGUAUUCCAUCCUGGGCACCACGCUGAAGGAUGAGGGCAAGCUCCUAGAGGCCAAGGGCCCCGUGACCGACGUGGCCUACUCCCACGACGGCGCCUUCCUCGCGGUGUGCGACGCCAGCAAGGUGGUCACAGUGUUCAGCGUUGCUGACGGCUACUCGGAGAACAAUGUUUUUUAUGGACACCAUGCAAAAAUCGUCUGCCUGGCCUGGUCCCCAGACAAUGAACACUUUGCCUCCGGUGGCAUGGACAUGAUGGUGUAUGUUUGGACCCUGAGUGACCCGGAAACCAGAGUCAAGAUCCAAGAUGCACACCGGCUGCACCAUGUCAGCAGCCUGGCCUGGCUGGACGAGCACACGCUGGUCACGACCUCCCAUGAUGCCUCUGUCAAGGAGUGGACAAUCACCUACUGAGGAGCCCCACCCCCGCCUCUGGAUGGACCGAAUCAGGGACUAGAGUUUAACUGCAGCGGAACAUGUCAUUUCUCUAUUUCUGUGACGCGCCCCCAUGCCCCCACCCCACCACAAGAGGCAGGAGGGCCCAGUCAUGACCCUCGUCUCUGCAGGGUGUCUGUACACGUUCUUCUGAAAGCUUUAGACAGUAACAGUUUGCACAUGAAAAAUAAAGCGAGCACCUAAACAAUGUGUGGAGCAUAACUAAAACCCACAGCCCAACCAAACCUUGAGAAUGCGAAACAUUCCAGAGGCAGUAGCCUCCAAAGCACACAGAGCCCCUGGCCCCGCCGCGGCUCUCACUAUCUGUCAGGGGAGGUUGUACAGGUGAAUGAGCCGGGGGGCUCAUGUUCCUGCCUGCAGAACAUUUCUGUACUAGUGAGAAGAGGGAAUAUGCAUUGCAGUUCAGCAAAGCCGGAAUUCUGUGUUGAACAGAUGUCUGUCUCCCUAGUGUGUGACUCACACCUUGUGGCUGCCUUCAGAGCGCCACCUCCAGAUCAGAUGGGGACACACAACCCCUGGAUAUGUUUCAUUGUCAGAUUUUGUGCUUGAUUUUAAGAAUGGAAUUGUGGGUAUCUUUCCUUUUUUUUUAAUGUAUCUUAACUGUUGCCUGUCAGUGUUUACAAACUAGUGCGUUGACGGCACCGUGUCCAAGUUUUUAGAACCCUUGUUAGCCAGACCGAGGUGUCCUGGUCACCGUUUCACCAUCAUGCUUUGAUGUUCCCCUGUCUUUCCCUCUUCUGCUCUCAAGAGCAAAGGUUAAUUUAAGGACAAAGAUGAAGUCACUGUAAACUAAUCUGUCAUUGUUUUUACCUUCCUUUUCUUUUUCAGUGCAGAAAUUAAAAGUAAGUAUAAAGCACCGUGAUUGGGAGUGUUUUUGCGUGUGUCGGAAUCACUGGUAAAUGUUGGCUGAGAACAAUCCCUCCCCUUGCACUUGUGAAAACACUUUGAGCGCUUUAAGAGAUUAGCCUGAGAAAUAAUUAAAUAUCUUUUCUCUUCA